ACUUACUCCAACAGCAGUCAAGAGAAUGAACAGGAGGGCAUGACAAGAGGCAGAAGACAGAAGGCAAGAAGACCACUCAGCAUUACAGAAGCCCAACAAACAGAUAUUUUCAGUUAAAAUAAGAUAGAGGCAACAAAAAGUAAUAAGGAAUGACCUGAAAUAUCAUGAGGGAAAAUGUACAAGGCAGUGACAGACUGGAUGUUGGCAGUGAAGUACAGAGUGAAGCGGAGGGCAAUUCCCAGGUUCCUGAAGGUUUCAUGAGGAAAGAGUGGUGCCAUUAAUCAAGCUCUUGUUCAGCUUCUGGAAUUUCUGAGCAGCCCUCGUCAGUACAAGAUGGACCCCGUAGUCUUGAGUUACAUGGACAGUCUACUGCGGCAAUCAGAUGUCUCACUAUUGGAUCCGCCAAGCUGGCUCAAUGACCAUAUUAUUGGGUUUGCGUUUGAGUACUUUGCCAACAGUCAGUUUCAUGACUGCUCUGAUCACGUCAGUUUCAUCAGCCCUGAAGUCACCCAGUUCAUCAAGUGCACUAGCAACCCAGCAGAGAUUGCCAUGUUCCUUGAACCACUGGACCUCCCCAACAAGAGAGUUGUAUUUUUAGCCAUCAAUGAUAACUCCAACCAGGCAGCUGGAGGAACCCACUGGAGUUUAUUGGUCUACCUCCAAGAUAAAAAUAGCUUUUUUCAUUAUGAUUCCCAUAGCAGGAGCAACUCAGUUCACGCAAAGCAGGUAGCAGAGAAACUGGAGGCUUUCUUAGGCAGAAAAGGAGACAAACUGGCCUUUGUGGAAGAGAAAGCCCCUGCCCAACAAAACAGCUAUGACUGUGGGAUGUACGUGAUAUGUAACACUGAGGCCUUGUGUCAGAACUUCUUUAGGCAACAGACAGAAUCACUGCUGCAGCUACUCACCCCUGCAUACAUCACAAAGAAGAGGGGAGAAUGGAAAGAUCUCAUUACCACACUUGCUAAAAAGUAGCUAUUGAAGUAUAUUUGCGACUUUUGAAGGCUCCUCUUUCUGCCCUUCCCCAUUUGUUGGAUGGCUGCAAUCUCAGUGCCUGAGGGAAGAUGCCUAGUAGAGGAAAGCUUAAUACUCUUUUUCCUGAAAGAAUAUCAUCCUCUGCAUUAUCCCCAUGGAACGUUUCACUUUAACCCUGACUGGGGAGCAAUAUGUUCUGUGAAAAUAUCUUGAAAUUGUACACCAAAACCUUACAACCAACUUAUUUGAACAUUUAUUACACACAGGGUUUACGUAAGACUUUUCUUAUUGGUAUAUAAUUAAUUUCCUUUGGUCUCCCUUAUCCACAUUGGCUUAUUCUGGAGGAAAAGCAGUGAUCUGUAAAACAAAUCAAGAAUAUAUUAAAUCUAGAGGAAUGCAGAGAAGAAAACUAUAAAACAGAACCAAAAACUUGUUGCACAGCCUACAUAAUUAAGAGAUCAACUGGCUGGAAGCAGAUCAAGGCCUAACUUCAUUCAAGACCUAAAUAUUAUGAGACUCAGUUAUUCGGUUUUAUGUGACAUCUCUUCCAUUCACCAUGCACAGGCUUUUCCAGCUAUCUAUAUAAUGUUUGCAAAUAUUUGAUAAAGAUGAUGUUACCCUAUCUUCCUCCAUCUGAUUCCUGGAAUGCUUGAAGAAAGGGGAAAUCUUGAGUAACCUCAUUAAAAUUAAUGUCUGGUGGACCUCUCAGUUUGCUCACUGAUUGGGUAGACUUGCUACUCUGGAUUAAUAACUGCUUUUCUCUGCCUUGUCUAUUAGCCAUGCACACACUUCCUCCUUAUAUCCAAAGUUCUUUGGUUCUAAAAUUCAUAGUUGAUACCUUCCCAAGGUUACCUGUUGUUUCAGAUAAACAUUUGUUCUUCCUGAUAGUUAUAGGUUUUCCUCUCUGUCCUUAAUUCUGGCAGAAUUGUUUUUAGUUAUGUCAUGGUAAUUUCAGGAUGAUUUUUGUAUCUGAAACUUAACAGACUUAGAGUUGGUUUGUUUUUUAAAUAUAAAGGAAGAAAAGUGACCUUUCUCAGCCCUUUUACUUAAUUAAAAAUGCAGGGAAUGUAAUUUGUAAAAUGUGGAACCAAGAGUAGAACGAAAUACUAUCCCUCCAGAAGCACUGAUGUGUUUCAGUUGUUUCAAAUAGUAAACAACCAGAUGACAUGUUAGGUACACAAAUUAAUUCUAUUCCUAAUGAGAAUUAGAUUGCAAGGCCUAUGAGACUUGAAAACCAAAGAUGAGCUUCAGCCAUGAAACUUAUUUCAGCUACCUCCCCAGCCUAACCCUGCCCCCAGCCCUCAUGGCCCAAAAUAACCUCACCACUCAGUGACCACAGAGAAAGUAACUUGGUUCCUUUUAGCCGAGAAGGGAAAACACAGUAAGGGUAAAUAAGUACAGGUUACAUAGCAGGCCUGAGUGAGCAGGAGCUGAAACUAAAAGUCAAAGAGAAAGCUAUCAAAAAAAGUUUCCAUUUCAAGUCGGUACAUUUUGGAUAAAAACCAGUCCUAAUGGAAGAUGGGGCUAGGAAAAAGAUUAGGAACUGGCAGUCAUCCAUAGAGGUGAAAUACAGAGGGAGGGACAGCAAGAGAAGUGACAAAGGUCACUGAUGAUAGGCCACAAGUGUAGAUAAAGAUAAGAAAACAAUGUUAUUUCAGUGACUGUUGACUUAGGCAGCUAAUCUAGACUAUUAAAGUCAAAUCCUCUCUGGGAAAAGUUAUCUUUCUGACAAUGCAAAGUAUGUUUAUUUAAAUAUCAGAGUAUCUUCAAUCUGAGAAUUAAAGCAUAUGAAAGCAAUCUUUCCUAACUCCCUACGAUUCAUCUUAUAAGUAAAUUUAUAAGUAAAUUUUUAAACUACACUAGUCUUUUAAAUAUAUAUAGAAAAAUAUAUAUACACACGUAUAGACAUGUAUAUGUAAUCUAUCUACAUAUAUAUAAAAAAUGCAUUUUCCAAAUGCAUUAGCCUGAUUGGACUGUGCCACAGAUUAGUGUCCUCCUAUGAAAUUUUGAGUAUGUCAUUUGUAAAUGUUAGCAUUAUAAAUUGCAGGAGAAUUUAAGAAUUGACUUGUAUUUCACUGGAUACUAUAGUACCCGGUAAGUUACACACCUGCUUGACCACAUACCAUUCAUGUUACAUGACACAAAAUAGGAAAAAAUCUUUUGCUGGUAUUGCGUUCCCUUCUCUCUUAGAGUCAAAAGGAUCUAUUCUGCAAAAUUAAUCAAAAUAUUCAAAAGGAAGGCAGGUUUUUCAAAACUGGGCUAAGCAAUUAUCAAACUGAACUAACCUGCUUUCAGAUAUCCUGUUGUAUUGCCCGGUAAGUAUAGUCACACUUGUCCAACCCGUGUCUCAAUAUGGAAUUCAGAAAAGUUACCAUAUAUAAACCCAGCUAUAAAUGGUUGUAGAAAAUAUAAGUAUCAGUGGGUUUCCUAUGUAAUAGUGUUUAAAACACAAAUAUUUCAACCAUUUGGCAAGGUAUAUGUUGAAGUUCACAAGCGCUGGUCCUAACCAGAUCAGAUAAAGUGGAUUAUGUUUCUGAUAUGUACCUAAUUAUUUUGACUAUACUAUAAUUUUACAAUAUGCAUAUUGACCGUAUGUUUUAAUAACACAUUCCAUUGAAAUGACCAAGUAGAAUUUCUCAGUUACAUGGGGCAGGCCGGGCGCAAUGGCUCAUGCCUGUAAUCCCAGGACUUUGGGAGGCCAAGGCAGGCAGAUCACCUGAGGUCAGGAGUUCAAGACCAGCCUGGCCAACAUGGCGAAACCCCGUCUCUACUAAAAAUACAAAAAUUAGCCGGGCAUGGUAGGUGGGCGCCUGUAAUCCCAGCUACUCAGCAGGCUGAGGCAGGAGAAUCACUUGAACCUGGGAGGCGGAGGUUGCAGUGAGCUGAGAUUGUGCCACUGCACUCCAGCCUAGGCAACAGAGCGAGACUCUUAUCUCAAAAAAAAAAAAAAAAGUAUUUACAGAAAUGUACAUGCUAUGGUGUUAGAGCAUGAAUGUCAAAUCCAGGGUCUGUCAGAUUCAGUAGUCUCAUCUACAAAAUAAACCUUGUUUUCCUUCUGUCCUACUCAGUUCCAUUUUAAGACUAACAACAAGUUUGAAAACUUAGUUUUAUAUUGCUAUGCAGCUAAACAGCUGUGUAAAAAAUGGCUGAUAAUUACUGUUAUGUACAAAAGAGAAACUUAUUCAAGGAUGGUGAAUAGCAACAACUAACCUUUUUAUCACUCUGUAAUGUGCAGGGUACUUUAUGCACACAUAUUACACAAGUACCUUGCAUAUUAUAUAUGCAUCAUUAUAUAUAUUACCAUAUAUAUAAAGUAACUUGUACAUUUUUGAGGUUCUAUAGAAAUAUAUAAUCUCAUUAAUUCUUAUGUUCUCAUGUUUCAACAGGUACUGUUAUUCUCAUUUUAUAAAUAAACUCAGAAGCUCAGUCA